UCCACCGGCCUUGGCCUCCCAAAGUGCUGGGAUUAUAGGCGUGAGCCACCGUGCCUGGCUGAAAAUUUUUCUUUUAGUCAUAUUUUCCAUGCACUGUUUAGAAGUACUGGACGUUAUAUACAAAGUGCCCACCAGGCUUCACUUGAGAGAAAAACCUUUCUUCUCAGGAUUCCAGCCACAACCCACAAUUGUAUGACAAAGUGCAGCAAGGUGCUCCCCAAAUCUGCAAACAAAAUAGUCUCUCUAUUUGGGAUCUACAGUCCCUUCUAGAGCAGUUAGACUAGAUUUCUACAAAAAUCACUUCAGGACAGCAAUCAGUUAUUUCACCUCCUUCAGUGCUCCUGUCAUCUUCAGAUCUGACACGGAUUCAGAGAUCACGGGGCCCAUAAACCCAACCAGGAUCAUACAUGUGCAUUGAUUAAACUUGAGAACUUCAAUUCUCUCCCUCCUCCCUUUGCCCAAAUGCCCGCAAAUGUGCAUAGCUCACCAGCCCUCCAAGACCUAAAUGUGCAGUUCCAAAUUCUGAAUUUAUUUUCUGGGAUUUGAGAGAAGAAAAGAACUUUUAUUUGAGAAAUACAUGUUCUUUUAAUGAUCAGACCCAGAGACUGGUUAAAAUGAGACCACAGUGAUGUACUGUUCCCGUCUUUGAACUAUUUGUCUUUUGAAAUUGCUUGCUAUUGGCACAAGUGGCUAUAAAUUAACCUAAUAAUGCCACACUGGACACUAUAAUCCACACCCAAUAGCUUAACAAUGUAUAUAACCAAUCACUAACCAAUGUUACUUCUGUAAAUAAGAAUUCCUGACAACUUUCUAUCCUGCCUUCCUUUUUGCCUUUACAAAUAUACUUGUAAUUGGAGUGUAUAUUCAGGUAGCUUUAUACUCCAGGAUUGCAGUCUUCAAGCUUUGGCCCCAGAAAACUCUCUACUUAUAUUAUGUUUAUCCCAGUAUUUCCUUUUAGGUCAAAAUAUUCUUAAGAAUGUGUUGAAGGAGCCUCCAUGAGGUGAUCUCUCCUCUGGUUUUACUCUGCUUACUCUAACCCCUAAGAAUGUAGAGGCACAUUGAUCCCACCUAGAAUCUGCAUACAAAAGUUGGCCUCUGCCUGGGAUUCCCAACACUGGACCAGACUUUGGGUUGAAGACAUACGAAAAACUCACAGAAGACAUUUUCUGCAUCAUGAGAGGUCAAUGUAGACAUCUUAAGCCCCAUUUUUAGAGUGGGGCCCUUUGAGUUUUCCAGAUCUUGUUCAGUGACCUGCUACAGCUGUGUGAGAGGCUUCUGAUGGGAACAGAAUCCUGUGGCAGAAUCUUUAAGUGUAAACAAGCAUCUUAGCAGUGGGAGGAACUCUUAACAUUCAAGGAUGUGGCCAUAGAAUUCUCUCCAGAAGAGUGGAAAUGUCUGGACACUUCCCAGCAGAAUUUAUAUAGAGAUGUGAUGUUGGAGAACUACAGAAACCUGGUCUCCCUGGGUGUUAGUAUCUCUAACCCAGACCUGGUCACCAGUCUGGAGCAAAGAAAAGAGCCCUACAAUUUGAAGAUACAUGAAACAGCAGCCAGACCCCCAGCUGUGUGUUCUCAUUUCACCCAAAACCUUUGGACAGUGCAGGGCAUAGAAGAUUCAUUCCACAAACUUAUACCAAAAGGACAUGAGAAACGUGGACAUGAGAAUUUAAGAAAAACUUGUAAAAGUAUAAAUGAGUGUAAGGUGCAGAAAGGUGGUUAUAAUAGAAUUAACCAAUGCUUAUUAACUACCCAGAAAAAAACAAUUCAAUCUAAUAUAUGUGUCAAAGUUUUUCAUAAAUUUUCAAAUUCAAACAAAGAUAAGAUAAGAUAUACUGGAGAUAAAACCUUUAAAUGUAAAGAAUGUGGCAAAUCAUUUCACGUGCUCUCACGCCUAACUCAACACAAAAGAAUUCAUACUGGAGAGAACCCCUACACAUGUGAAGAAUGUGGCAAAGCCUUUAAUUGGUCCUCAAUUCUUACUAAACAUAAGAGAAUUCAUGCCAGAGAGAAAUUCUACAAGUGUGAAGAAUGUGGUAAAGGCUUUACUCGGUCCUCACACCUUACUAAACAUAAGAGAAUUCAUACUGGAGAGAAACCCUACAUAUGUGAAAAAUGUGGUAAAGCUUUUAACCAAUCCUCAACCCUUAAUUUACAUAAGAGAAUUCAUUCUGCACAAAAAUACUACAAAUGUGAAGAAUGUGGUAAAGCCUUUAAGUGGUCCUCAUCCCUUAAUGAACAUAAGAGAAUUCAUGCUGGAGAGAAACCCUUCUCAUGCGAAGAAUGUGGCAAUGUCUUUACCACAUCCUCAGACUUUGCUAAACAUAAGAGAAUUCAUACAGGAGAGAAACCCUACAAAUGUGAAGAAUGUGGAAAAUCCUUUAAUAGGUCCACAACUCUUACGACACAUAAGAGAAUCCAUACUGGAGAGAAACCCUACACAUGUGAAGAAUGUGGAAAAGCCUUUAAUUGGUCCUCAACCCUUAAUGUACACAAGAGAAUUCACUCUGGAAAAAAUCCCUACAAAUGUGAAGAUUGUGGCAAAGCCUUUAAAGUGUUUGCAAACCUGCAUAAUCAUAAGAAAAUUCAUACUGGAGAGAAACCCUACAUAUGUAAACAAUGUGGCAAAGCCUUUAAACAGUCCUCACACUUGAAUAAACAUAAGAAAAUUCACACUGUAGAUAAACCCUACAAAUGUAAAGAAUGCGGGAAAGCUUUUAAGCAGUACUCCAACCUUCCUCAACAUAAGAGAACUCAUACUGGAGGAAAAUUUUAGAAAUGUGAAGAAUGUGGGAGCCUUUAAGUCUUCCUCAGUCUUUUCUAAUCAUAAUUCAUACUGGAGAGAAACUCUACACAUGAAAAAAUUGACAAAGCUUUUAACCGCAACUCAAUCUGUUCUAAACAUAAGAGAAAUGGUAUUGGUGAGAAGCCAUAAAAAUAUGAAAAAUGUGGAAAAGCCUUCAAAUGCUUGUCACAUAUUACUGAAUAUAAUUCUUACUGCAGAAAACCCCUAGGAAUAUUAAAAGUGUGGCAAAACCUUUAACCAAUGCUCAUAUCUCUUUGCACAUGAUAGCAUUUAUACUUGAGAAAAAUUGUACAAAUAUAGAAAAUGUAGAAAAGCCAUUAAUGCCUACUCAUGUGUUACUAAAUAUCAGAGAGUUUGUACUUAAUAAAAGGAUUAUAAAUGUAGUAUUUGUUGAAAGACCUAUUAGAAAAUACAGGUCUUAAAAGUGAAGAAGAGUAUUCUGAAGAUAGACAAUAGAAAUAGUAAGAGGGUUGUAGUACCUGUACUUGCAUCAUGGGUCUUAUUGUGCAUAUUUCAUACUAGAAGAAAACCCUGAAGCAGUUGCCCAAACUUUCUUUGACAUUAGAGAAUUUAUAUUGGAAAGAAAUUUUACAAAUGUAAUAAAUUUGGAAAAGCAUUUGUUCAAAAACUAUAGCUUAAAAAAAACCAGUUUAUACUAGAAGAUAUUUUGUAGAUGCGGUAAGUAUGAAAAGAUAGUCUGAAAUUAAGACUAAAUGUCAGAAUAUUUACAGUAGAAAGAAAAAGGCAUUAACACUUGAAACAUUACAGUAUAUCAGAGUGUAAAGUAUAAAAAAAUUCCAAAGCUGAAACUGUUAGAUAAUUUCUUUCUAUAUAAGUUGAAAAGGAGUAGCUUUUUGAAAUUAUUCCAUUGAAAUUAUACUUUUUUUACCUGAAAAAAUUAUAGAUUUUUUGAAAAGCAAAUUCAACUCUAAAAUUACUUCAUACUGAUUCAACUUAUUGUUUAUAUGAAAGCAUGUGAUGAAUUGUUGCAUCAGAGGUAUGAGUGAUUCUUUUUAGGUGGGCAUCAUUCAUGAACUUUUUUUUUUUUUUUGAGACGGAGUCUCGCUCUGUCGCCCAGGCUGGAGUGCAGUGGCGGGAUCUCGGCUCACUGCAAGCUCUGCCUCCCCCUGGGUUCACGCCAUUCUCCUGCCUCAGCCUCCCAAGUAGCUGGGACUACAGGCGCCCGCCACUACGCCCGGCUAAUUUUUUGUAUUUUUAGUAGAGACGGGGUUUCACCGUUUUAGCCGGGAUGGUCUCGAUCUCCUGACCUCGUGAUCCGCCCGCCUCGGCCUCCCAAAGUGCUGGGAUUACAGGCGUAUUCAUGAACUUUUACAUGAAUGAGUAAGGACAUUGAAAGAUGCAUGAGAUGAUGCAUACAUCUUUGUGGUUGACUUAUCAUUGCAUGAUGCAUGACGUACAUGUUCAGAGUAAUAUUCUUCUGCAUUAUAGUGAGAGAAAAAUCUUGAAUUUUAGUAAUAAAUUGCUUUUACCAGUUGCACAUUUAUGUAAUAAAAUACAGUAAAUUUUAAAAUUCUCUUUUAAGAUUGUGUGUGAACCUUACUCAAGGGUGUAGGUAAAAAAUGGUAACAGUAUACUUUUAGUAACAUAGUUUAAUGACAUUUCUAGUAAUUUCUUUUUCCAGUGGCUUUAAACAGCAAAUAAGUUGAAGAAUAUUGUUCUCAUGUUAAAUUUUUAUUAUUUUUUAUAUUUAAAUUUAUUUUUAAAAAUUUAUGUGGGUACAUGGUAUGUGUAUACAUUCAUGGCAUAGAUGGGUUACUUUGAUACAGACAUGCAACAUGUAAUCACAUCAGAGUAAAUGAGUUAUUCAUCACCUCAAGCAUUUAUCCUUUGUAUUACAAACAAUCCAAUUAUACACUUCAUUUUUAAAUGUACAAUUAAAUUAUUUUUUAUUACAGGUAAUUUUAUGAUUGUAUUUAGAAUUAUAUCAGAAUAUAAUUAUAAUUUAGACAUUUCUGUGUCCUGAAUAAAUAUGUUUUUAAAUGUUCCAUA